AGCGGACUGCGCAUGUGCAGGACCCAGCAGGUCUAGAGCUUUUCUGUGUUUCUCCGGACUUCGAGCCAUGGCGGUGACGGAAGCGAGCCUGUUGCGCCAGUGCCCCCUGCUUCUGCCCCAGAACCGGUCGAAAACCGUGUAUGAGGGAUUCAUCUCGGCUCAGGGAAGAGACUUCCACCUUAGGAUAGUGUUGCCUGAAGAUUUACAACUGAAGAAUGCAAGAUUAUUAUGUAGUUGGCAGCUGAGAACAAUACUUAGUGGAUACCAUCGAAUAGUACAACAGAGAAUGCAGCACUCUCCUGAUCUAAUGAGCUUUAUGAUGGAGUUGAAGAUGCUUUUGGAAGUUGCCUUAAAGAAUAGACAAGAGCUGUAUGCACUACCUCCUCCUCCCCAGUUCUACUCAAGCCUUAUUGAAGAGAUAGGAACUCUUGGUUGGGAUAAACUUGUGUAUGCGGAUACCUGCUUCAGUACCAUCAAGUUAAAAGCAGAAGAUGCUUCUGGUAGAGAGCAUUUAAUCACUCUCAAGUUGAAGGCAAAGUAUCCUGCAGAAUCACCAGAUUAUUUUGUGGAUUUUCCUGUUCCAUUUUGUGCCUCCUGGACACCUCAGGUAAAUUCUCCUCAGGUCACUGAUCAAGCAAAAAUGGAUGUGAAAAUUGCGGUUUUGCCUAGCUCCUUAAUAAGCAUUUAUAGUCAGUUUUUGGCAGCAAUAGAAUCACUAAAGGCAUUCUGGGAUGUUAUGGAUGAAAUCGAUGAGAAGACCUGGGUACUUGAGCCAGAAAAACCUCCACGGAGUGCAACAGCACGCAGAAUUGCAUUAGGUAAUAAUGUUUCCAUAAAUAUAGAGGUAGACCCCAGGCAUCCUACUAUGCUUCCUGAGUGCUUCUUUCUUGGAGCUGACCAUGUGGUAAAACCCCUGGGAAUUAAGCUGAGCAGGAACAUACAUUUGUGGGAUCCAGAAAAUAGUGUGUUACAAAAUUUGAAAGAUGUUUUAGAAAUUGAUUUUCCAGCUCGUGCUAUCCUGGAAAAAUCUGAUUUUACUAUGGAUUGUGGAAUUUGUUAUGCUUAUCAACUUGACGGUACCAUUCCUGAUCAAGUGUGUGAUAAUUCUCAGUGUGGACAACCUUUCCAUCAAAUAUGCUUAUAUGAGUGGCUGAGAGGACUACUAACUAGUAGACAGAGUUUUAACAUCAUAUUUGGUGAAUGUCCAUAUUGUAGUAAGGUAAGCAAAUUGUUAAUCACAUCUCAUAAAAUGUGCCUAGCUUUCAGUAAUAUGUUCUAGAAGAUAGAUCUAUAUAGUAUAUCAGUUUAUCUAAAACUUUUGAAACUCAUUCUCUGUAUUUCUAUUUUUCAAAUUCUCUGAUCAAAAACAUUAAACUCCUUUUCUAGAUUUCCUAGGUGAUCUGAAACUUCAGAAGUGUUUUCCAAACUGUACUAUGACACUAUUCUAUGACACUAUUUCUAGUACAAAGCAAUUUUAUUUUUUAGAGUGUCCACAAACUUUGUUAAAAUAUGUUCUCUUUUUAAAGCCAAUUACCUUAAAAAUGUCUGGAAGGAAACACUGAAAUAAGAAUACAACAUUUCGGUGAAGAGCUGGAAACUUAAAAAAUUAUCAAAAGGAAUUUUGGUAUCAUCUUCAGAGAAAAAAUAAAGCAAGAAAUACUAACAUCAAAAGGACAGGUAUGAUGAUGCGAUAAUAAUAAACAUCUGCGUUUGUCUCUUCACUAAGAGUAAACUGGGAAAUUGUAGGCCAAAGUCCAGUUGAACUUUCUAAGUCUGUGAUCCCCGUGCUGACUGUGGAAGUGUAUUUAUACCAAGAUGGAGAUCUUGACUUCUUGAAUAUAUCUGGACUGGUAAAAUCUUGAUGAGGCUCAUAAAAUGAGUUUGGGAAUUGUGUAUAGCUGAUUUUUUGUGGGAAACUGUUUACUUCAUUCAAAGGUUCUUGAGACUCUUGAUAUUUCUGUCUUCUCCUUGUGCUUUCCUAUGGAAAAAAUACAUAUAUAGUUUAGUUUGUUAGACGUGAGUUAUCCAAGUAUUUAUUUUGUGUAGUGUGUAAGAAUGCUAAAUAAAAUGUUAUACAAGA